AUUGGUGGUUGAGUCGUUACCUAGGAAACCAGCUGAUUACAAGGAAUUGGCACCAAGGGAAGGUAGGAGGUAUUCACGAAGAGUAUAAGCCUAACAGUUAGUUUAAUUGUAUAGUUUUAGCUGACUCACAAGUAAAUUUCAGCCAGGUGUUAGACUCAUUCUCCAGACUGACUAAGGCUGCAAAGGGCAAUAGUAAGAAUAGGGACUCUACAGGUAUCAUCAUAAAGAAGUAACAAGCAUCUGUCAACAGUCCAAAACCUCCAGCUAGCAAAAAGUGGGGGGAAAUGUGACUAAGAAAUAAAGUACUGUUGUUGCAGGUUAAAGUAAAACAACCAGUGGCUCCAGUUAUCUUUCCAUGGGUCUUGGGCAGACUUUUCAUGUAGUUAUCAGUUUGGUCCAACUGACUUGGGUGGAAGCCCUCUUCUUUUUGUAGUCAUCUGCUUCAGAAGGAUUCCUUGUCACCUCUUUUUGAGGUGUCCUGCUGGGACAGUCUUCCAGCAAUUUAAGAUUGGCGUAUGUCUCUAUGUUUGAGAGACAUGAAUACAGGGAUCAACACCCUAUUUUACUGUUGCAUUAGUUAUUAACAGCACCUGGCAAAAUUCUAUUUAUUGAGUUUAGAGGGCAGUUUUCCAGAAGACAGUCUCUGAAUUUUAAUAUAAAGGUUGUUUCAGAGGAAAUGCUUCCUGGACCUGUUUGAAUGGAAAACUGUGUGUACUCUGAGUUACAGUUAAUAACUGGAAAUGUAAUAAACAUAGUAACUUGAGAUGAUGGCAGUAUUCCCAGAUGUAUAGGAUGCCCAGAUUUUGGUUCAUAGAGUUAAUGAGCUCCAGGGGAACUGCCGUCACUUGUCAUUCAGGCAAAAGAGAAAAACAACAACAAAAAACCCUUUAGGCUAAGGAAGUCUCAGGAUUUCUGAAAGUUUAACCAACUUCAGUUUGAGAUUUCUAUUUGUCCUUUUUAUCUUACCUGAAGGCUAAGAGUGAUAAAGGCAAUAGAGAUUUUGAGUGAGAGGUACAGAUGCUCCCCGAUUUAUGAUGGGGUUACAUCCUAAUAAACCCAUUUAAGUUGAAAAUAUCAUAAGUCAAAAAAACAUUUAAUAUACCUAACCUACCAAACAUCAUAACUUAGCCCAGCCAGCUUAAACACGCUCAGAAUACUUAAUGUUAGGGUAGCUGACUGGGAGCUGCGGCUUGCUGUCGCUGUCCAGCAUCUCAAGAGAGUAUCAUACCGUAUAUCCCUAGACUGGGAAAAGAUCAAAAUUCAAAGUACAGUUUCUACUGAAUGCAUAUCACUUUUGUACCACGAGAAAGUCAGAAAACUUGUAAGUCAAGCCUUUGUCAGUUAGGAAGCAUCUAUAUUGUCUUACAAAUCUCUUUAGUAACAGUUCUAGGGAGGUAAGUGUUUCUGUCUCCAGAGAAGUAAUCACAGAUUUCCCAAGUAGGAAGCGCAAACUCAAGACACGUUUUGUUUUUUUUUAACCAUUGGUAUAGUUGAGGCUUUUCGACAAGCUAUAUUCAUCCUAAAAAUAGACUAUAAUUACCAAAUAAAAGCCUAUAUUGACAGAAUAACUAUUUUUGAAAAAAAAAACCUGUAACAUAUCUGUAAGUUCUUCUACAUGAGUAUUUUUUAAAGCUGCCAAUUAUAACCCAAUUCAUGACAUCAACUCAGUUUUUAAAAAAAGAUAUGAGGUACUGCAGUAUGAAACUUUUGUGGGUUUUGUUUUGUUUUUAAGCAAUUUGUGAUGUGUCUGCAUUUUUUCUUUGUAUUCUAUCUUGGGCUGAUUGAGCCUCUUAGAUCUGUAGGUUAAUAUUUUUCAUCAAAUUUGGAAAAUGCUUGGCCACUAUUUAUUCAAAAUUUCUGCCCCAGUCUCUCUCCUCUGCUUCUGGGACUCCAGUUAUAUACGUAAGAACACUGAAUGUUGUCUACAGGUCGUGGAGGCUUUGUACUCCCACUACACUCUUCUUCAUGUAUCCACACUUGACAAAUUACAAUUUGAACCUCCUCUGAGAAAAGAAACAGAAGCACGAGAUGAAAUGGGAUUGUCAUCAGACCCAAAUUUCAUGUUACAGUGGAAUCCUUUUGUUGAUGGUGCAAAUACUGGCAAAUCAACCUCAAAACGUGCAAUACCACCUCCCCUACCUCCUAAGCCAAGGAUAAGCAGUUACCCUGAAGACAACUUUCCGGAUGAAGAAAAAGCAUCAACCAUAAAACAUUGUCCUGAUUCAGAAAGCAGAGCUCCCCAAAUUCUCAGAAGACAGAGUAGCCCAAGUUGUGGGCCUGUGGCAGAGACUUCUUCUAUUGGAAAUGGUGAUGGUAUUUCAAAACUGAUGAGUGAAAAUACAGAAGGAUCAGCACAAGCACCACAGUUACCACGAAAAAAGGACAAACGAGACUUCCCUAAACCAGCCAUCAAUGGCCUUCCACCCACCCCAAAAGUUCUGAUGGGAGCAUGCUUUUCAAAAGUUUUUGAUGGCUGUCCUUUGAAAAUUAAUUGUGCAACAUCCUGGAUACAUCCUGAUACAAAAGAUCAGUACAUUAUUUUUGGAACUGAAGAUGGUAUUUACACACUGAAUCUCAAUGAGCUACAUGAGGCAACGAUGGAACAGUUAUUUCCACGGAAGUGUACUUGGCUGUAUGUUAUCAAUAAUACUUUAAUGUCAUUAUCAGAAGGAAAAACCUUUCAGCUCUACUCUCACAAUCUUAUAGCUUUGUUUGAACAUGCCAAAAAACCAGGAUUAGCUGCCCAUAUUCAAACUCACAGGUUUCCAGACCGAAUACUACCAAGAAAAUUCGCUUUAACAACAAAGAUUCCUGAUACAAAAGGCUGCCACAAAUGUUGCAUAGUCAGAAACCCUUACACGGGACAUAAAUACCUCUGUGGAGCUUUACAGUCUGGAAUUGUUUUACUUCAGUGGUAUGAGCCAAUGCAGAAAUUCAUGUUGAUAAAGCACUUUGAUUUUCCUUUGCCAAGUCCUUUGAAUGUUUUUGAAAUGCUGGUGAUACCUGAACAGGAAUACCCUAUGGUCUGUGUAGCUAUUAGCAAAGGCACUGAAUCGAAUCAGGUAGUUCAGUUUGAGACAAUCAAUUUGAACUCUGCAUCUUCAUGGUUUACAGAAAUUGGUGCAGGCAGCCAGCAGUUAGAUUCCAUUCAUGUAACACAGUUGGAGAGAGAUACCGUUUUAGUGUGUUUAGACAAAUUUGUGAAAAUUGUAAAUCUACAAGGAAAAUUAAAAUCAAGUAAGAAACUGGCCUCUGAGUUAAGUUUUGAUUUUCGCAUUGAAUCUGUAGUAUGCCUUCAAGACAGUGUGUUGGCUUUCUGGAAACAUGGGAUGCAGGGUAAAAGCUUCAAGUCAGAUGAGGUUACCCAGGAGAUUUCAGAUGAAACAAGAGUUUUCCGCUUAUUAGGAUCAGACAGGGUUGUCGUUUUGGAAAGUAGGCCAACAGAAAAUCCUACUGCACACAGCAAUCUCUACAUCUUGGCUGGACAUGAAAAUAGUUACUAAGCAACAGAAACUGAUCUCAAAUGACAGGAAAAUGAAUAUACUCCAUUGAAAGGAAAAAUAAGGAAAUUCAAUACAAACUGCACUAUGAUUUGCUUUAACUAUUAUGGGUUAUAUUGCAAAUGAUCUGUACUUUAGGGUAGAAUUCAAUAUUUUCUGCAGCUGGAAACAGCUAGUCUAUCUCUUGCCACUGUGUGGUGGUUAUAUCAAGUUUGCUUAAUAAAAGCUAUGAGACAAAUAGUCCUCUAGUUCCAGGAAACACAGUCUUUUUUUAAAAAAAACAAUGUUUGUAACAAGGGUGCCAUGGUAUUUUUAGAUAACUCGUGAUUAUCUUAAGAGAGGUAAAUUUAGUGAUCAUUUUAUAUCAUGUCUUAUUCCUUCUUAAUGAACAUAAUUUGUUAAAUUCUCAAGCAAGGUUUUCACUUUUAUAUUGGCCAUUCUGUAUGUUUUUGUAAAACAGAAUAUUUAAUCCUUAUUUAUUAAUCUCUUGCUGGAGUGGUGUAAUGUAUCUAACUUUUAGCAAAGGAGGGUUGCAGAGCAGCUUAAAUUUUUUUUAUAAUGUAUAAGAAUUUUGUUUAUCUUUUAAGAGUAGUAAAGUACUUUGAGUGUUUGGGGGUUCAACACACACAUGCAAUUUUGCUUAACAAAAGUAUUUUAUAAUACAGUUUCAUACAGAAUUACCUUAAAAGGGAGUCUUAUGUUUUCAACUACAGAUAGUUGUAAGGGAUCAUACAGAAGAUAUUGAUGAUAGUUGAAAUAUUCUUAGAAGGGGUGUGUAUGUCUAGCUGUGUCUACCAUGUGUAUGUAUUCUUGACAAGCAGUAUAAAAUACCUGUGAUUUUUCUUUACAUUAGGGAUAAUGCAUAAGGAAUUAAUCUUCAUAUAUAUUAUCAUCCCUAAUGUAGCAGGGGGAAGUAUUUAAUUGCCCAUGAUAUGUAUUUUACUUAUACUAUGCCAGAGAGGAAACUAUAAAGUAAUUACACAUGUAAUCUUGGGUUUUUCACAUAUGUAGGUAUUCAUUUUGAGUAGGUUGAAGAAGAAAAAAAAUAUUUAAAUGAAUUGAAUUCCUGAUGGGAUAGUAUCAAUAAGUAUUUAAAAGCCAGUAUUCUAAAAAUAAUAAAGGGUAGGGUCAUUUUUGAGUUUGUUUUUCUUUUGCUAUUGUUAAUAUUCAAAAUUAAAGUGUUACAUUGGUACCUGUUGUCUUAAUGCAUUUAUUGAGAACAGCAUUGAGAUGAUGAACAAGGGGUUAGCAAUAGCAAACUCUAUAAUUAUUUUGACUAAUUACUUAAGAGGAAAACAGUAUAAGUAUCUCAUUCAGUAUUUAGCAAUUCUGUAAAAUAAGUAUUAUCUCUAUUUUUCAGAUGAGGAAGUAAGGGUUUAGCAAGGUUAAGAGAUCUAUCCAAUUUACACAGCAAGUUAGUAGUUGAGCCUGACCAUGAGUCUUCUGACUCUGUUCUUUUCACUAUGCAAUACGCAAACAAUAAAAUGUUAUACAAAUGGAA